GAGAGUCGUUGGGCUCCGCCCUAGCUUGGCCUGGGCGCCGCAGACCGGAGCCAGAAGCACGCUCGCGGGGGCUUGCGACCGCCUUCCUGGGAAGCUGUCCCCUGGCAGGCAUGGGUGCUUUACAUCCUGAGCUGGGAAGCUGUUUGCUUGAGGGUUUUUCUCAAGGAUCGAGGCGCGGUGUGAGCCCGUCCAUGCUCGGUCCUGUAGAUCCCGGGAGGCCAUGUUAUAAAAGGAGACUUGCUGGGAUGUGACGGGUUGCCACUUGAAAUAUCUUCCAUUUGGAUAAAGUAGGAAUAUUUAUACAUGUGCCCCAAACGUCCCUCCGUGUCCCCCACCCCCAAGCGGAAAUGUGAAAAUGGGCCUUGCCUUUGCUGGUGCCCAAGGACCGCCUUCCACUGCAGUGACGGCGCUGGCGGGGGAGGCGCUCUUGAGCCCCUCCCGAUUGUCCCUCUGCCUAGCAAGCAAGUUGCGACUGGCCACAAGGCAGGCCUCUUCCGACCAAGGUAAGGGGCCUGGAUACCAAGAAGUGACUGCUCAUCUAAUCCAUAAAGCUAUGUUAACAGAUUGGAGGUAGUAGCAUUUUCAUUACAAGUGACUAAAAGAACAGCUGUUUACCCCUGAUCGUGCAGCAGUGCUUGCUGUUCCUUAGAAUUUUGCCUUCUGUUUGCAGACAAGGUCCCAAAGACAGCAGAAAAUUUUCGUGCUCUGAGCACUGGAGAGAAAGGAUUUGGUUAUAAGGGUUCCUGCUUUCACAGAAUUAUUCCAGGGUUUAUGUGUCAGGGUGGUGACUUCACACGCCAUAAUGGCACUGGUGGCAAGUCCAUCUAUGGGGAGAAAUUUGAAGAUGAGAACUUCAUCCUAAAGCAUACGGGUCCUGGCAUCUUGUCCAUGGCAAAUGCUGGACCCAACACAAAUGGUUCCCAGUUUUUCAUCUGCACUGCCAAGACUGAGUGGUUGGAUGGCAAGCAUGUGGUGUUUGGCAAAGUGAAAGAAGGCAUGAAUAUUGUGGAGGCCAUGGAGCGCUUUGGGUCCAGGAAUGGCAAGACCAGCAAGAAGAUCACCAUUGCUGACUGUGGACAACUCGAAUAAGUUUGACUUGUGUUUUAUCUUAACCACCAGAUCAUUCCUUCUGUAGCUCAGGAGAGCACCCCUCCACCCCAUUUGCUCGCAGUAUCCUAGAAUCUUUGUGCUCUCGCUGCAGUUCCCUUUGGGUUCCAUGUUUUCCUUGUUCCCUCCCAUGCCUAGCUGGAUUGCAGAGUUAAGUUUAUGAUUAUGAAAUAAAAACUAAAUAACAAUUGUCCUCGUUUGAGUUAAGAGUGUUGAUGUAGGCUUUAUUUUAAGCAGUAAUGGGUUACUUCUGAAACAUCACUUGUUUGCUUAAUUCUACACAGUACUUAGAUUUUUUUUACUUUCCAGUCCCAGGAAGUGUCAAUGUUUGUUGAGUGGAAUAUUGAAAAUGUAGGCAGCAACUGGGCAUGGUGGCUCACUGUCUGUAAUGUAUUACCUGAGGCAGAAGACCACCUGAGGGUAGGAGUCAAGAUCAGCCUGGGCAACAUAGUGAGACGCUGUCUCUACAAAAAAUAAUUAGCCUGGCCUGGUGGUGCAUGCCUAGUCCUAGCUGAUCUGGAGGCUGACGUGGGAGGAUUGCUUGAGCCUAGAGUGAGCUAUUAUCAUGCCACUGUACAGCCUGGGUGUUCACAGAUCUUGUGUCUCAAAGGUAGGCAGAGGCAGGAAAAGCAAGGAGCCAGAAUUAAGAGGUUGGGUCAGUCUGCAGUGAGUUCAUGCAUUUAGAGGUGUUCUUCAAGAUGACUAAUGUCAAAAAUUGAGACAUCUGUUGCGGUUUUUUUUUUUUUUUUUUCCCCUGGAAUGCAGUGGCGUGAUCUCAGCUCACUGCAGCCUCCGCCUCCUGGGUUCAAGUGAUUCUAGUGCCUCAGCCUCCUGAGUAGCUGGGAUAAUGGGCGUGUGCCACCAUGCCCAGCUAAUUUUUGUAUUUUUAGUAUAGAUGGGGUUUCAUCAUUUUGACCAGGCUGGUCUCAAACUCUUGACCUCAGCUGAUGCGCCUGCCUUGGCCUCCCAAACUGCUGAGAUUACAGAUGUGAGCCACCGCACCCUACCUCAUUUUCUGUAACAAAGCUAAGCUUGAACACUGUUGAUGUUCUUGAGGGAAGCAUAUUGGGCUUUAGGCUGUAGGUCAAGUUUAUACAUCUUAAUUAUGGUGGAAUUCCUAUGUAGAGUCUAAAAAGCCAGGUACUUGGUGCUACAGUCAGUCUCCCUGCAGAGGGUUAAGGCGCAGACUACCUGCAGUGAGGAGGUACUGCUUGUAGCAUAUAGAGCCUCUCCCUAGCUUUGGUUAUGGAGGCUUUGAGGUUUUGCAAACCUGACCAAUUUAAGCCAUAAGAUCUGGUCAAAGGGAUACCCUUCCCACUAAGGACUUGGUUUCUCAGGAAAUUAUAUGUACAGUGCUUGCUGGCAGUUAGAUGUCAGGACAAUCUAAGCUGAGAAAACCCCUUCUCUGCCCACCUUAACAGACCUCUAGGGUUCUUAACCCAGCAAUCAAGUUUGCCUAUCCUAGAGGUGGCGGAUUUGAUCAUUUGGUGUGUUGGGCAAUUUUUGUUUUACUGUCUGGUUCCUUCUGCGUGAAUUACCACCACCACCACUUGUGCAUCUCAGUCUUGUGUGUUGUCUGGUUACGUAUUCCCUGGGUGAUACCAUUCAAUGUCUUAAUGUACUUGUGGCUCAGACCUGAGUGCAAGGUGGAAAUAAACAUCAAACAUCUUUUCAUUA